AAGUGUUUGAAGCAGGUCAUGCCUGGCUGCAGGAGAACCUGACCUCUCCAGAUUUUUGGGGCUUUUCUUUUUUUCCAACAGACACAGGCAUGCUGGCUAGAAUACUGGAGGGAGGUGGGUGAUAGGGUGGGCUGCCCCUCAAACCUGUGUGCUGUGUCCCACAGCAUCAUUCCCCAGACAUGGGGCCAGGUCGGAGCUGAUUCCUGCCCUGCGUUUCGGAGAUCUUGAACAGAAGCCAGGGAAUCUUCAGACACCGCAAAAAGAAAUCCCUUGAGAAAAGGACCAGAGUUGUCAUAAUAAGGACACCCACUGAGGCCUUGCUCUGUUCCAGGUACUGUGCCACAUGCUUCUUGAGCCCUUGCAGCAACUCCCUGAGGUCAAUAUCAUCAUUAUACCUAUUUUGCAGAUGGGGAAACUAAAGCCGGGAGAGGCUGAGUAACUUGCUGAAGUCCACACAGCUGGGGAGUGGAUUCAGACAGAAGGAAAUAAAAUGAGGCAUUCCUGCAUCGCAUCCGGCAGAACGUGGCCGACUCAGUGGAGAAGGGCCUCACGGAGGAGAAUGUCAAGGUCCUGUUCUCGAACAUCGAAGACAUCCUGGAAGUUCAUAAGGAUUUCUUGGCCGCCUUGGAGUAUUGUUUACACCCGGAGCCGCAGUCUCAGCAUGAACUUGGGAAUGUUUUCUUAAAAUUCAAGGACAAGUUCUGCGUGUACGAGGAGUAUUGCAGCAACCAUGAGAAAGCCCUGAGGCUGCUGGUGGAGCUGAACAAGAUCCCUACCGUGCGCGCCUUCCUUUUGAGCUGCAUGCUUCUGGGAGGCCGGAAGACCACGGACAUCCCUUUGGAAGGCUACCUGUUGUCUCCGAUCCAGAGGAUCUGCAAGUACCCGCUCCUCCUUAAGGAGCUGGCCAAGAGGACUCCCGGCAAGCACCCAGACCACCCCGCGGUCCAGAGUGCCCUGCAGGCCAUGAAGACCGUUUGCUCCAACAUCAAUGAGACCAAGCGGCAGAUGGAGAAGCUGGAAGCCCUGGAGCAGCUGCAGUCCCACAUCGAAGGCUGGGAGGGUUCCAACCUCACAGACAUCUGCACUCAGCUCCUCCUGCAAGGGACUUUGUUAAAGAUCUCUGCGGGCAACAUCCAGGAAAGGGCCUUCUUCCUCUUCGACAACCUUCUCGUCUACUGCAAGCGGAAAUCCAGGGUCACCGGGAGCAAGAAGUCCACCAAGAGGACCAAAUCCAUCAACGGCUCCCUCUACAUCUUCAGGGGUCGAAUCAACACUGAAGUCAUGGAGGUGGAGAAUGUGGAAGAUGGGACAGCGGAUUACCAUAGCAACGGCUAUACCGUCACCAACGGCUGGAAGAUCCACAACACGGCCAAGAAUAAGUGGUUUGUCUGCAUGGCCAAGACGGCAGAGGAGAAGCAGAAGUGGCUGGAUGCCAUCAUCCGCGAGCGGGAGCAGCGCGAGAGCCUGAAGCUGGGCAUGGAGCGUGAUGCCUACGUCAUGAUUGCGGAGAAGGGGGAGAAGCUGUACCACAUGAUGAUGAACAAGAAGGUGAACCUCAUCAAGGACCGCCGGAGAAAGCUGAGCACUGUCCCCAAGUGCUUUCUUGGCAAUGAGUUCGUUGCCUGGCUCCUAGAAAUUGGUGAAAUCAGCAAGACGGAAGAAGGAGUCAACUUGGGCCAAGCCCUGUUGGAGAAUGGCAUCAUCCACCAUGUUUCCGACAAGCACCAGUUCAAGAAUGAGCAGGUGAUGUAUCGCUUCCGCUACGACGAUGGCACCUACAAGGCCCGAAGUGAGCUGGAGGACAUCAUGUCCAAGGGUGUGAGGCUUUACUGCCGUCUUCACAGCCUCUACACCCCGGUGAUCAAAGACCGUGAUUACCACCUGAAGACCUACAAGUCAGUGCUUCCCGGGAGCAAGCUGGUGGACUGGCUGCUGGCUCAGGGAGACUGCCAGACUCGGGAGGAGGCAGUGGCGCUCGGCGUGGGUCUGUGCAACAAUGGCUUCAUGCACCACGUGCUGGAGAAGAGCGAGUUCAGGGAUGAGUCCCAGUACUUCCGCUUUCAUGCUGACGAGGAGAUGGAGGGGACCAGCAGCAAGAACAAACAGCUUCGCAACGACUUCAAGCUGGUGGAGAACAUUCUGGCCAAGCGCCUGCUGAUCCUGCCCCAGGAGGAGGACUAUGGCUUUGACAUCGAGGAGAAGAACAAGGCUGUGGUGGUGAAGUCCGUCCAGAGGGGCUCGCUGGCUGAGGUGGCUGGCCUGCAGGUGGGGAGGAAGAUCUACUCCAUCAAUGAGGACCUGGUGUUCCUGCGGCCGUUUUCAGAGGUGGAGUCCAUCCUCAACCAGUCCUUCUGCUCCCGCCGCCCUCUGCGCCUCCUGGUGGCCACGAAGGCCAAAGAGAUCAUCAAAAUCCCCGACCAGCCGGACACACUGUGCUUCCAGAUUCGUGGAGCUGCCCCACCGUACGUCUAUGCUGUGGGGAGAGGCUCUGAGGCCAUGGCUGCAGGGCUCUGUGCUGGUCAGUGCAUUCUGAAGGUCAAUGGCAGCAACGUGAUGAACGAUGGUGCCCCUGAGGUCCUGGAGCACUUCCAGGCAUUCCGGAGUCGGCGCGAAGAGGCCCUGGGCCUGUACCAGUGGAUCUACCACACCCAUGAGGAUGCCCAGGAAGCACGAGCCAGUCAGGAGGCCUCCACUGAGGACCCCAGUGGCGAGCAGGCCCAGGAGGAAGACCAGGCUGAUUCAGCCUUCCCACUGCUGUCCCUGGGUCCCCGGCUGAGCCUGUGUGAGGACAGCCCCAUGGUCACCCUGACUGUGGACAACGUGCACCUGGAACACGGCGUGGUGUAUGAGUAUGUGAGCACGGCAGGCGUCAGGUGCCAUGUGCUGGAGAAGAUCGUGGAGCCCCGCGGCUGCUUCGGCCUCACCGCCAAGAUCCUCGAGGCCUUUGCUGCCAAUGACAGCGUCUUCGUGGAGAACUGCAGGCGGCUCAUGGCCCUGAGCAGCGCCAUCGUGACCAUGCCCCACUUUGAGUUCCGCAACAUCUGUGACACCAAGCUGGAGAGCAUUGGCCAGAGGAUUGCCUGCUACCAGGAGUUUGCAGCCCAACUGAAGAGCAGGGUCAGCCCACCCUUCAAACAAGCCCCCCUGGAGCCCCACCCGCUGUGUGGCCUGGACUUCUGCCCCACCAAUUGCCACAUCAACCUCAUGGAAGUGUCCUACCCCAAGACCACCCCCUCAGUGGGCAGGUCCUUCAGCAUCCGCUUUGGACGCAAACCCUCCCUCAUCGGCCUUGACCCGGAGCAAGGCCACCUGAACCCCAUGUCGUACACCCAGCACUGCAUCACCACCAUGGCUGCUCCCUCCUGGAAGUGCUUGCCUGCUGCAGAGGGUGAUCCCCAAGGCCAGGGUCUCCAUGAUGGCAGCUUCGGGCCAGCCAGUGGGACCCUUGGUCAGGAAGACCGGGGCCUCAGCUUCCUACUCAAGCAGGAGGACCGUGAGAUCCAGGAUGCCUACCUGCAGCUCUUCACCAAGCUGGAUGUGGCCCUGAAGGAGAUGAAGCAAUAUGUCACCCAGAUCAACAGGCUGCUGUCCACCAUCACAGAGCCCACCUCGGGUGGGUCCUGCGACGCAUCCUUGGCUGAGGAGGCCUCCUCCCUGCCCCUGGUCAGUGAAGAGAGCGAGAUGGACAGGAGUGACCAUGGGGGCAUCAAGAAGGUGUGCUUCAAGGUGGCCGAGGAGGACCAGGAGGACUCAGGCCACGACACCAUGAGUUAUCGCGACUCCUACAGCGAGUGUAACAGCAAUCGAGACUCGGUCCUGUCCUACACCAGCGUGAGAAGUAACAGCUCCUACUUGGGCAGCGACGAGAUGGGGUCUGGAGAUGAGCUGCCCUGUGACAUGCGGAUCCCAUCUGACAAGCAGGACAAGCUUCAUGGCUGCCUGGAGCACCUCUUUAACCAGGUGGACUCCAUCAAUGCUCUCCUCAAGGGGCCAGUCAUGAGCCGGGCUUUCGAAGAGACCAAGCAUUUCCCUAUGAACCACAGCUUACAAGAGUUUAAACAGAAAGAAGAGUGUACAAUCCGUGGCCGGAGCCUGAUCCAGAUUAGCAUCCAGGAGGACCCCUGGAACCUCCCCAACUCCAUCAAGACCCUGGUGGACAACAUUCAGAGAUAUGUGGAAGAUGGGAAGAACCAGCUGCUCCUGGCCUUGCUGAAGUGCACAGACACGGAGCUGCAGCUGCGCAGAGACGCGAUCUUCUGCCAGGCCCUGGUGGCCGCCGUGUGCACCUUCUCCAAGCAGCUGCUGGCGGCCCUGGGCUACCGCUACAACAACAAUGGCGAGUACGAGGAGAGCAGCCGCGACGCCAGCCGCAAGUGGCUGGAGCAGGUGGCGGCCACGGGCGUCCUGCUGCACUGCCAGUCCCUGCUCUCGCCAGCCACAGUGAAGGAGGAACGGACCAUGCUGGAGGACAUCUGGGUGACGCUGUCAGAGCUGGACAAUGUCACCUUCUCCUUUAAGCAGCUGGACGAGAACUAUGUGGCCAACACCAACGUCUUCUACCACAUUGAGGGCAGCCGGCAGGCGCUGAAGGUCAUCUUCUACCUCGACAGCUACCACUUCUCCAAGCUGCCCUCCCGCCUGGAGGGUGGGGCCAGCCUGAGGCUGCACACAGCGCUGUUCACGAAAGUGCUGGAGAACGUGGAGGGGCUGCCUUCUCCAGGCAGCCAGGCCGCGGAGGAUUUGCAGCAGGACAUCAACGCGCAGUCCCUGGAGAAAGUUCAGCAGUAUUACCGCAAACUCAGGGCAUUUUACCUGGAGCGGUCUAACCUGCCCACGGAUGCCAGCACCACGGCGGUAAAGAUAGACCAGCUGAUCCGCCCCAUCAAUGCCCUGGAUGAGCUCUGCCGCCUCAUGAAGUCCUUUGUCCACCCAAAGCCUGGUGCUGCUGGGAGUGUGGGCGCCGGCCUCAUCCCCAUCUCCUCGGAGCUCUGCUACCGCCUGGGGGCCUGCCAGAUGGUCAUGUGUGGCACAGGCAUGCAGAGGAGCACCCUGAGCGUGUCCCUGGAGCAGGCGGCCAUCUUGGCACGGAGCCACGGGUUGCUGCCCAAGUGCAUCAUGCAGGCCACGGACAUCAUGCGGAAGCAGGGCCCAAGGGUGGAGAUUCUGGCCAAAAACCUGCGAGUCAAGGACCAGAUGCCCCAGGGUGCUCCGCGCCUCUACCGCCUCUGCCAGCCGCCGGUGGAUGGGGACCUCUGAACACCCAAAUGCCCCACGCUGGGCCGCGGCCUCUGGAGCUGGGAUUUGGGAGGACACAGCAGGCAGCGCUGGCCUUCUCCAGGGAUGGCCCAAGGCUUCCGCAGCCGCCCGUUCCGGGACCUGCCCAGCGUCCUCCCUGCCUCCUUCCGGGACAAGCCUGGCCACCCUCGCUGUGAUGACGAGCUGGCUGAUUGGCCCUGGGCCGGCCCAUUCUUCACACGCCUGCCAGAAGCUGGAGGGGUGCUGGAGACCCAUAGAGCUGAUGGGAGCAGCUGGUGCCUGGCCUUCGGCUCCUGCGUCCCCAGAACCCAAGGGAACGUCAUGGAGGCCACAUGGGGCCACCCGGCUCCCUCGGGAUGGCUCCGCCUGCACUUUUGAAACCCCGGUUUCCUUCAACGUCCACAUUCCAGGUGACCACACGUGUCUCCUCCUCCUCAUCUUAGCUUCCAGGUUCACCCUAACCCUGUACUAACCUGCUUGGUGGACUUGGAAAAGACUUGGCUCUGUCGGGAAAGGAGAGACGGGGCCUCCAUCACGCCUGUUACCAGAGGAUCCCCGAGAGCCACACCAGCUCUGGACAUCACCGCCCCUGGAACUGGGGCCACCAGCCCUGGGCACGAGAUUUGCUCUGACUUUAUUUAUAUGGCAUGAAAUCUCUGGUUUAUUUUGGGAUUUUUUGUUGUUGGUGUUGUCAAAGUUUGUUUUUUCUAAAGUUGUGUGAUUAUAUAUUUGACAUUUUACAUUUCAAAGAAAGGUAUGUUGUCUAACAGGGGACCAACAGAAGGUAGUAUUGACAACUGUUCCUGCUUCUACUAAAAAAAAAAGAGCACAAAAGAAAAACUAAAUUAUUGAAAAAUUAAAAAAUGUCAUUGUUUCCUGUUUGUUAAUAUUAGGGUUGUAAGGUGUCGUUUUGAGGUAUCGACUGUGAUUCCUUCCCCCACCCUCCAUUCUCCAGCGGUUGGCCGGUGUUAGAACUCGCUCUCUUUGAGUGACUGGCUACAAGGGCCUGAGAGGUGGCCAGCCAGGGUUGGAGCUGGAGGGGAUGGAGCCCCACCUGAGGUGCCGUGUCACACGGGUUAGAGGGUCACUGGGAAACACCGGGCGGUGGCUUCUGUGAUUUAUUUUCUUGAUGGUAACUUCUCAGAGCAGGGCGAUUGGGACAUCACCAGCCAGAGCACAGGAAGCCACCCUGCCUGCUGGGGAGGAGGGACCCACACAAGCCCCCUCGGCAGUUUGUCCCCCCAGCUUCGGUAUGCCUUCAGGGAAAGGUCACAGCUGGGGAGGAAGCGGGGGGACGCCUGUCACCCCUGGCAGGUGGUGAGUUCAGGUGGGGGCUCCCUGCUGCCCCCAGGCCUGGGAGCUUGAAGCCCUCCCGGCAUCUGGCAUCCGAGCCUCCCGCCCUCCAGGGUGCGCUUCCCUCUCUUGCCGCAGCAUACACGAGGGCAGGCAGUGGCCUUGUCACUGUAUCUUGCAUCAGAGACAAAGGAGGACCCGCUUUAGCCCUGCUGCGGGAAAUGGGGGAGGGCCCAGGGCCAGCGCAUUGUGCACUGGUUUACUUUAAAAUGUACAGAUUCUUCUCGUUAAAUUCUUGAUAGAUUUUUUAUUAUUAUUAAAAGUCAGUUUAUAAUACAAA